CCUCACAGCCCUGAGUGAGGGUGUGCAGCCUCCUUGGGCAAGAGGAUGCGGGCUCUGGGAGGCUGCGUCGCACAUCUCCAGUCCCCACUGCAGGGCCUCUCACCGGCUGGGGCAGUGACCCCUGGUCGGAAGCACCUCAGUGCUGCUCAUGAUUGCAGAGGUGGCCUCACCAGAUAGAGGGUCCUGGAGGGCGUGGGGGCUUGGUCUCUGACUGCCAGCAAAAGAAGCCGACAUAGAGGCAGCAGGCGACAAACACUGAGGCAACUGACUUGCCCGAAUUUAACCCUCAGGUUUUUUAAAUAAAAUGCAAGUGCAGGGGCUUGGGCUCGGGACUCCUGGAGCCCCGUGGGGCUGAGCGUGGAUGGUGCUCGGUGUCCAGCUACACUCCCAAACCGCAUCCCGAGCGUUUGCGGGGCGGAGGGGCCCCAGGGCGACGGUUCCAGAACAGACCCAGGCGGCUCCGGUCAGCAGCAGCCCCGCUGCUUUCCAACAGCGCGGGGACCCCCAUCCCCGCCAGCCCCAUCUCACUGUCCCUCUCAGGUCAGAGGAGACCGUAGAGGACCGCGUGGCACCAGGAGCUGCCAGGAACCAGGGCGACCUAGAAGAAACCGGGAACCUGGCGUCCCGCGGGGACGCAGCCCCAGGAAAGGGGCUGCCGCCGCCAGCAAGUGAGCUCAGCUCAGCCCGGGCGUCCCCUCCGCAACGAGGCCCGGAUCCCUGCUUGGCUCCCGGAGCCCGGACUGUGCCUUCCGCAAAACGGCUGCGCUCUAGAAAGUGGCCUCCACAGUGCACUUCCCGGCAGCAUGGAGUCGGCAGUGGCAGCGUUUCUAUCCGGCUCUGCGGGGCUGGGUGUGAACGGGACUCUCCCAUCCCGCUGUCCUCCAGGAGCCGGACCUCUCACCCCGAAGACUUUGCCGAAGACGCGGCCCCCUGGUCAGGGGCAGAAAACAGAUCCAGGCCGCCCCGCUCCUGCUGGGUGGUGGAGAAGGUGGAGGGCGGGCAGGUGCUAAGUGCUACUGUGAAAAUAAAAAUCAUCAUAAUAAAGAACGAAUGGGUUUCGUAUCUCUUAAUUCUCACCAUCAAUAGGGUAUUCGUGGGCCCAUUUGACAGAGGAGGAAGCCACCUGGAGAAGCUCCCUUCCUUGAGAGCCAGGCCCUUCCCUGUCCAGCCCCGUGUCACCUGCUUCCCUUACAGCUCGCUCUCUCUCCCUCUCAUCUUCAUAACCCGCUUCCCCCUGGGAGCAGGAAUUUGA